GAGACGUGACCACCCGCCCCGCAUGGGGCCCCAGUCCCAGCUGCUUGAUCCGGCUCAGCCCCGAGGUGUUUGCAGCAGCUCUUUAUGAAAGUCCAGCCAUCUGUUACCUGCGUUGCUUCCUGGGGAGGGAUAGUCCACCUGGAGGCAUUCGGAGACCCAGUGAUUGUGCUCCGCGGAGCCUGGGCUGUGCCCCGCGUUGACUGCCUCAUAGAUACCCUACGAACCCCAAAUGCCAGCUGCAUGAGAAAAGGGACUCACCUUCUGGUUCCCUGCCUGGAAGAGGAAGAGCUGGCAUUGCACAGGAGACGGCUGGACAUGUCUGAGGCACUGCCCUGCCCGGGCAAGGAGACCCCCACCCCAGGCUGCAGGCUGGGGGCCCUGUAUUGGGCCUGUGUCCACAAUGAUCCCACCCAGCUCCAAGCCAUACUGGAUGGUGGGGUCUCCCCAGAGGAGGCCACCCAGGUGGACAGCAAUGGGAGGACAGGCCUCAUGGUCGCAUGCUACCACGGCUUCCAGAGUGUUGUGGCCCUGCUCAGCCACUGUCCUUUCCUUGAUGUGAACCAGCAGGACAAAGGAGGGGACACGGCCCUCAUGUUGGCUGCCCAAGCAGGCCACGUGCCUCUAGUGAGUCUCCUGCUCAACUACUAUGUGGGCCUGGACCUGGAACGCCGGGACCAGCGGGGGCUCACGGCGUUAAUGAAGGCUGCCAUGCGGAACCGCUAGUGACUGCUCCUCCCACAACCCCAAGAUGGGAGAGGGAGAUGGUGAGAAGAGAAGAACCAGGAGAGGGAACCAGCCGAUCAUCCCCACCCACCUGCCCCAGAGGGUGCAGCUCAGGCCUCUGCCUGUCCUGGGCAGCCUGCACCGCUGCUCUGCUCAGCUCCUUGGAUUGAGGAGAUCCCUAUUCUGCCCUAGGUGGAGCCCCACAAUAGGUCUCUCUGAAGUCUUUUCCCCUCUCUGGACCUAAGUGUCUUAAUCUCUCUUAAACAGGAGGUUGCAACACUGGCCUCCCUGAUUCCACCUUCAACAGGAUGGGACUCUAUGGCUUCGAAUGUAACCCACAUCAGUCUUGCUCCUAAAGAAUCUGCCCUUCCACAAAUCACCAACCCCUAUCCCGCCCCAUGUCACCCCCUGUGCUCCUUCCCAGGUGCUGACCUGACAGCAGUGGACCCUGUUCGGGGCAAGACGGCCCUGGAAUGGGCAGUGCUGACCGACAGCUUCGACACCGUGUGGAGGAUUCGGCAGCUGCUGAGGCGGCCCCAAGUGGAGCAGCUUAGCCAGCACUACAAGCCCGAGUGGCCGGCCUUGUCCGGGCUCGUGGCCCAGGCCCAGGCCCAGGCCCAGGUUGCCCCUUCACUCCUAGAACGGCUGCAGGCUACCUUGAGCCUCCCCUUUGCCCCGUCUCCUCAGGAGGGGGGUGUUCUGGACCACCUUGUGACUGCCACAACCAGCCUGGCCAGUCCCUUCGUCACCACUGCCUGCCACACUCUGUGCCCUGACCAUCCACCUUCGCUGGGCACCCGAAGCAAGUCCGUGCCAGAGCUGUUAGGUACUGCCCCGCCCCCUCCCCUGGUUCCCCAGUCCCCGCCAGGGAGUCCCCAGAGGUCCCCGUGGGUCUUCGUCCCCUACCAGAGCCCUCAGGGCAUAUUGAGCAAGUGCCUUCAGUGGCUACAACCCAGGGAUAGCACCAGCCCCAGGCCCCAAGUCCCCAAGAUCCUCCUCUCCAAGGCAUCCUCAUCCUCCCACCAGUGCCAGCCGAAGCCCAGUCCUUCAGGACACCAAAGUCUGGCCCUUCCUCUCUGGCGAUACCAGGAGCUCAGGAUAGAGAAGAGGAAACAGGAGGAGGAGGCCAGAAUGGCACAGAAGUAGGGGAAGAUGGGAUAGGACAGGCUGGGAACAGGUAAUCAGGCCCCUCCCAGGGCUUCUUUCCCCUCUGGAGUGCCUCCGGCCUCCCCAUCCACCUCUGCCUAAGUAAAUCUGCUCUCAACCUAUAUAUAUACAAGGUCAUUCAUUCUAGCAUUGUUUGCAAGAGUGAAAGAGUGGAAACACCCGAAGUGUCCAUCAGUAAGGGACAGGCUAGAUUGAUUACGGAUGUAAUUGCUGUCCAUCCAUACAGAGCAUACUCUACAGUGUAUUCUAAAAUAAGACUAAGGAAGCUGUUUAUAUUCUGAUAUGAAACUACCAUCAAGAUGUAUAAAGUAAAAAUAACUAAGGAGUGGAACAGUGUAUAUGGCAUAUUAUUAUUUGUCGAAGUAAAAUUUUCACGAAGAUAAACAUGACUAAGACAAAUA